CCCCUCCCUCUGGAGUUUCCAACGGUAGAAUAGAGCCCUGUCUAGUAUUUGACCAAAUAUGGUGGCAUCUCUCAUGCUCGAGCCCCAGCCAGCAUCUCAGUUAUGCUGUGGAAGCCUGCCCCGGACAGAUUAAUCUUGUGACAUUCAGGAGCGCCUCUCACCCUGCCUUCUUCCCCUCGGACGAUUCCUGUAAAUGGCCAAGACCGGCCCUCAGCACGACAGGGCCGUCCUCAGUAUCUGUUCACAAUGCCCCUCCUCUGUCCUCCUCACAUUCCCUCCCGCCAUUCCUGCCUCCCUGGGUGGAUGUGCCCGCUUACAUUGGGCUGGGCUGUUCACCUGAGGUGAGAGACAUUGGCCAGAGGAGGUGGUCAGUUGAGCAUGUGAUUCCAGGACCUUUGGACCCUGAGGUCAUCCGACCUCACAAACUUGUGGCCUGAAUCUUGGAGGCCUAGACCUCUCUCAGCAGCCAGGAGGGUGGGCCUGAGGGGGUUGAAGGGAGAGUCAGUAGAGAAAUGAGAACCAUGCUACCUCUAAUGCUAAUUAGAACAACUAAUGUUUAUAAUAAUUAUACAAUUAUUUUAUAAUAAUCUCUAUAAUAAAUAGCUAAGUGUUUAUUGAGCACUUACUAUGUGCCAGGUACUGUUGCCAGCUAUUUAACAUAGGUGAUUUCCUUUAUUCCUUAUAGCAGUUUUAAGAGGGUGCCAUGAUUCUUCCCAUUCUAGAGAUGUGGGAACUGAGGCUCAGAAAGAUUUCAGGAGGGAAUGGGCCAGGCCACCGUCUACUUCUGGAUACACCCACCAUUUUAUGGAGGAGGGAACUGAGGCUGACAGUAAAGCUCACAUGCAGCCACACAGUCUCUGAGAGCGGAGACCACCCCAGGAGGGAGAGUGCUGUGUCAGGAAGGCCAGGACAAUCAGCCCUGUUUCUUCUUACCAUUUCCAUCUUCCUGGGGCUGGGCCAGCCCAGGAGCCCCAAAAGCAAGAGGAAGGGGCAAGGGCGGCCUGGGCCCCUGGCCCCUGGCCCUCACCAGGUGCCACUGGACCUGGUGUCACGGAUGAAACCGUAUGCCCGCAUGGAGGAGUAUGAGAGGAACAUCGAGGAGAUGGUGGCCCAGCUGAGGAACAGCUCAGAGCUGGCCCAGAGAAAGUGUGAGGUCAACUUGCAGCUGUGGAUGUCCAACAAGAGGAGCCUGUCUCCCUGGGGCUACAGCAUCAACCACGACCCCAGCCGUAUCCCCGUGGACCUGCCGGAGGCACGGUGCCUGUGUCUGGGCUGUGUGAACCCCUUCACCAUGCAGGAGGACCGCAGCAUGGUGAGCGUGCCGGUGUUCAGCCAGGUUCCUGUGCGCCGCCGCCUCUGCCCGCCACCGCCCCGCACAGGGCCUUGCCGCCAGCGCGCAGUCAUGGAGACCAUCGCUGUGGGCUGCACCUGCAUCUUCUGAAUCACCUGGCCCAGAAGCCAGGCCAGCAGCCCGAGACCAUCCUCCUUGCACCUUUGUGCCAAGAAAGGCCUAUGAAAAGUAAACACUGACUUUUGAAAGCAA